AUGCAGGGUAGCCGGAGGGAUUGCCGGAUGCAUGCCACUGCCACUGGACCUGGCUUCUCUGGACUCCCAUGGGCAGUGCACCACCCUCUGCACAGCCCUAGCCACUGUUAUCCCACAAGCGCGGUCCGAAGUCCACGUGCCCACUCUGCCCAGCCUCCUUCCUCUGUCCCCUCAGGGCCUUUCACUCCUUGUGACAACUCUAGGUGCUGUCUGGGCUCCUGGGGAACCCCCGACCCUUCCAGCCAUGGAAUCAGCUCCCGGCAUGCGGGUCAGGCUGGACCCAUGGCUCUGCACCUCAGCCCAGCAGCUUGGGGCUGCCCUGUAGGAGCCGACACGACCUCCCUUCCAUUCGGCCCCCUUCCUAGGACCCACUGUAUGCCAGGGUGGGGAGACGGAGGCAGAGAGAAAUCUGGGAGAUUUCCGUCCUGGAGGGGCUCAGCCAGAGCAGGAAGGUGCCCAGGCAUGACAAUCCCAGACUCCCAGAACCACCUGCCUGCUGUGGGGUGGGGAAGCCCUCAGAGAGCCCAUCCUUACAGUCAGAGCAGAGAUGAAGGUUCCUGUGGACCGAGGCGGUGGGCCAAGCGCAGAACAGGAAGCUGGAUGCAGUCUGGUGUGUCAGGAGCUCCUGGGCAAAGACAUCGAGCUUAUUGGGGUCAAGGCUGGGGAGAGAUGGGGCUGAGUCCCAGGGACCUUGGACGGAGCUGAAGGGAGAUAGGAA